GCAACUCACACCUGCCUCAGACCAGAGCUCUGUGCGGGUGACGGCGCACGCAUUCCUUGUGUCCCCGCCUGUCUUGGACAGAGCAGAAGCCACACCUGCCAGACCAGUGCCACCGGGACAGCUGCUGGUGGCCGGCCCCGGGGAGGGAUACCUGCUGGGUGAAGCACAGGCCGGGCCGGGCCCGGAGAAGAGGAAGCAGACACUGCCACGGCAGGGCAGCCCAGGGCCUUGGAGCCCAACCGUGGCCGGCGAGGAGGACCACGCCCAGGCCCGCUGACCCCCGGCCACCAGCUCAGAGACAUGUCGUCAGGCCAGCAGGUGUGGCACACGGCUGUGCCACCCCCUCGCCGGAGCAGCUCCAUAGCCUCGAUGCCCAGGUCCCCCAGCUCGGCCGGCAGCCCCAGGUCCCCUGGCACCCCUGGCUCGGAGAGGGUGGCCUCCCCCCUGGAGUGCUCCAUCUGUUUCUCAGGCUAUGACAACAUCUUCAAGACACCCAAGGAGCUCUCCUGCACCCACGUCUUCUGCCUGGAGUGCCUGGCCCGGCUGGCGGCUGCUCAGCCUGUGGGCCGCCCCGGUGGUGAGGCUGUACCUUGCCCCUUCUGCAGGCAGCCCACGGCCGUGCCGCCCGCCGGAGCCCCCGCGCUGUGCACCAGCCGCCAGCUGCAGGCCCGGAUGCCGGCGCAUUUGCGGCGUGAGGAGCCUGUGUGGCUGGAGGGCACCAAGCUGUGCUGCCAGCCACUGCCCACCACACCUGGCCGCGAGCCCGGUUUCGUAUGCGUGGACGUGGGUUUGAGCAAGCCUGCCGAGCCGCCCGCGCCCGCCCGGGACCCUGCCCCCCGCCGGGGCCGCCUGGCCCGCUGCUGGGCGCGCUGCAGGGACUGGAGGCGCAUGGCACUGGUCUCUGCCCUGCUGCUGAUGCUCUUCUGUGUGGCACUCUGGCCGGUGCAGUGCGCGCUCAAGACCGGGAACCUGCGCUGCCUGCCCCUGCCCCCCCGGCCCCCGGCCACCAGCACAGCCGCCUCCCCCCUCGGGCCUCUGACUGAUAAUUAGGGCCAGCAGCCUCUGCCCAGGUCAGCCGCCCUCGCCCAGCUCCAUGGGGCGUCCCCCACUGGGGGGCCCAAGGGCACAGCAGCCACUGGAAGUCGGUCCCCGAGGACGCGAAAGGAGCCUGGCAUCUCUGAGGACUCCACCGGGGCCCCACCAAGACCAGGCUCCAUUUAGCUUGUCCACCCCUCAUUCUCCAGGCUGGGUCCUGACGGGGUGGACAAGAGGAUCCCCAAAGCCUCCAAGAACCACAGUCUCACCGGGCGCGGUGGCUCACGCCUGUCAUCUCAGCACUCUGGAGGGCUGAGGCAGAAAGACCACUUGAGGUCGGGAUUUUGACACCAGCCUGGCCAACAUGGUGAAACCCCAUCUCUACUAAAAAUACAAAAAUUAACCGGGCAUCGUGGUGGGUGCCUCUUAGCUACUGGGGAGGCUGAGGCAGGAGAACUGCUUGAACCGGGGAGGUGGAGGUGGCAGUGAGCCAAGAUUGCACCACUGCAUCCAGCCUGGGCGACAGAGGGAGACCCUGUCUCAAAACAAAACAAAAAAAAACAGGCUCGUACAGGAAGGGUCCAGGAGAGCAGCUGGUCAGCAUCCCCCCCACCCACACACCCUGUGAACUGCCUGCCAGGGAAGCCCCUUGCCAAGAAGGAAGGGGCCUUGCCGUGCUUCCACUCAUGCUGACAUUUCCCCGCAGGGCUGGUCCUGCCAUUGGGUGGGGGUGCUCAUCUUGCCCUCGGACUGUGGGGAGAGAGUGGAGGCAGGGCAGCCCCCCAGUGCAAGGUAACCACAGAAACUUCCAGCUACCCCUCCAACCUUGUGAAUUGUACCUUUUAAAAUAAAUUAUUUGUAUCCA